AUCCGGGCUCCCGGCAGCGGCGCUGCGGCGGCUCGCGGGAGACGCUGCGCGCGGGGCUAGCGGGCGGCGGAGCGGACGGCGACGGGGCGCUCUCGGGCUGCCGGCGGGGCCGAGCGCCGCGCGUCCCGAGCAUGGCAGGCUCCCUGCCUCCCUGCGUGGUGGACUGUGGCACCGGGUAAGAGCAGCUCGGCGCCCACCCCCGCUCCUCCGCGGCCCCGCUCCCGGCCCCUGGCGUCCACCUCGCCUGGAGGUCGAGCUGCGUCCGUCGCCCCGGGCUUGAGCCCCGCGAUCACCUGGGCAGGUAUACCAAGCUUGGCUACGCAGGCAACACUGAGCCCCAGUUCAUUAUUCCUUCAUGUAUUGCCAUCAGAGAGUCAGCAAAGGUAGUUGACCAAGCUCAAAGGAGAGUGUUGAGGGGAGUUGAUGACCUUGACUUUUUCAUAGGAGAUGAAGCCAUCGAUAAACCUACAUAUGCUACAAAGUGGCCGAUACGACAUGGAAUCAUUGAAGACUGGGAUCUUAUGGAAAGGUUCAUGGAGCAAGUGGUUUUUAAAUAUCUUCGAGCUGAACCUGAGGACCAUUAUUUUUUAAUGACAGAACCUCCACUCAAUACACCAGAAAACAGAGAGUAUCUUGCAGAAAUUAUGUUUGAAUCAUUUAACGUACCAGGACUCUACAUUGCAGUUCAGGCAGUGCUGGCCUUGGCGGCAUCUUGGACAUCUCGACAAGUGGGUGAACGUACGUUAACGGGGAUAGUCAUUGACAGCGGAGAUGGAGUCACCCAUGUUAUCCCAGUGGCAGAAGGUUAUGUAAUUGGAAGCUGCAUCAAACACAUCCCGAUUGCAGGUAGAGAUAUUACGUAUUUCAUUCAACAGCUGCUAAGGGAGAGGGAGGUGGGAAUCCCUCCUGAGCAGUCACUGGAGACCGCAAAAGCCAUUAAGGAGAAAUACUGUUACAUUUGCCCCGAUAUAGUCAAGGAAUUUGCCAAGUAUGAUGUGGAUCCCCGGAAGUGGAUCAAACAGUACACGGGUAUCAAUGCGAUCAACCAGAAGAAGUUUGUUAUAGACGUUGGUUACGAAAGAUUCCUGGGACCUGAAAUAUUCUUUCACCCGGAGUUUGCCAACCCAGACUUUAUGGAGUCCAUCUCAGAUGUUGUUGAUGAAGUAAUACAGAACUGCCCCAUCGAUGUGCGGCGCCCGCUGUAUAAGAAUGUCGUACUCUCAGGAGGCUCCACCAUGUUCAGGGAUUUCGGACGCCGACUGCAGAGGGAUUUGAAGAGAGUGGUGGAUGCUAGGCUGAGGCUCAGCGAGGAGCUCAGCGGCGGGAGGAUCAAGCCGAAGCCUGUGGAGGUCCAGGUGGUCACGCAUCACAUGCAGCGCUACGCCGUGUGGUUCGGAGGCUCCAUGCUGGCCUCGACUCCCGAGUUCUUUCAGGUCUGCCACACCAAGAAGGACUAUGAAGAGUACGGGCCCAGCAUCUGCCGCCACAACCCCGUCUUUGGAGUCAUGUCCUAGUGUCUGCCUGAACGCGUCGUUCGAUGGUGUCACGUUGGGGAACAAGUGUCCUUCAGAACCCAGAGAAGGCCGCCGUUCUGUAAAUAGCGACGUCGGUGUUGCUGCCCAGCAGCGUGCUUGCAUUGCCGGUGCAUGAGGCGCGGCGCGGGCCCUUCAGUAAAAGCCAUUUAUCCGUGUGCCGACCGCUGUCUGCCAGCCUCCUCCUUCUCCCGCCCUCCUCACCCUCGCUCUCCCUCCUCCUCCUCCUCCGAGCUGCUAGCUGACAAAUACAAUUCUGAAGGAAUCCAAAUGUGACUUUGAAAAUUGUUAGAGAAAACAACAUUAGAAAAUGGCGCAAAAUCGUUAGGUCCCAGGAGAGAAUGUGGGGGCGCAAACCCUUUUCCUCCCAGCCUAUUUUUGUAAAUAAAAUGUUUAAACUUGAAAUACAAAUCGAUGUUUAUAUUUCCUAUCAUUUUGUAUUUUAUGGUAUUUGGUACAACUGGCUGAUACUAAGCACGAAUAGAUAUUGAUGUUAUGGAGUGCUGUAAUCCAAAGUUUUUAAUUGUGAGGCAUGUUCUGAUAUGUUUAUAGGCAAACAAAUAAAACAGCAAACUUUUUUGCCACAUGUUUGCUAGAAAAUGAUUAUACUUUAUUGGAGUGACAUGAAGUUUGAACACUAAACAGUAAUGUAUGAGAAUUACUACAGAUACAUGUAUCUUUUAGUUUUUUUUGUUUGAACUUUCUGGAGCUGUUUUAUAGAAGAUGAUGGUUUGUUGUCGGUGAGUGUUGGAUGAAAUACUUCCUUGCACCAUUGUAAUAAAAGCUGUUAGAAUAUUUGUAAAUAUC